CCAUUUCCCAGCAGAGCCCCUGAGAUCUGGAGACUGCCCCAGCCUCAGGCUCUGUGCAUCUCCCCCGAGCCCCCACCACAUAUGUGCGGAGGCCCCUGGGGGCCCAGGCCUGUCCUCAGUCCCGACUGGGCUCUACCUGAGGACCCUGGGGAGCCUGGGCCUGGCCCUCCUCAGAGCUUGGGGCUUCCUUGGUCGCACCCACCACCUGCCUGCCCACUGGUCAGCCUUCAGGGACCCUGAGCACCGCCUGGUCUCUUUCCUGUGGCCAGCCCAGAACUGAAGCGCUGCGGCAUGGCGCGCGCCUGCCUCCAGGCCGUCAAGUACCUCAUGUUCGCCUUCAACCUGCUCUUCUGGCUGGGAGGCUGUGGCGUGCUGGGUGUCGGCAUCUGGCUGGCCGCCACACAGGGGAGCUUCGCCACGCUGUCCUCUUCCUUCCCGUCCCUGUCGGCUGCCAACUUGCUCAUCAUCACCGGCGCCUUUGUCAUGGCCAUCGGCUUCGUGGGCUGCCUGGGUGCCAUCAAGGAGAACAAGUGCCUCCUGCUCACUUUCUUCCUGCUGCUGCUGCUGGUGUUCCUGCUGGAGGCCACCAUCGCCAUCCUCUUCUUCGCCUACACGGACAAGAUUGACAGGUAUGCCCAGCAAGACCUGAAGAAAGGCUUGCACCUGUACGGCACGCAGGGCAACGUGGGCCUCACCAACGCCUGGAGCAUCAUCCAGACCGACUUCCGCUGCUGUGGCGUCUCCAACUACACUGACUGGUUCGAGGUGUACAACGCCACGCGGGUACCUGACUCCUGCUGCUUGGAGUUCAGUGAGAGCUGUGGGCUGCACGCCCCCGGCACCUGGUGGAAGGCGCCGUGCUACGAGACGGUGAAGGUGUGGCUUCAGGAGAACCUGCUGGCUGUGGGCAUCUUUGGGCUGUGCACGGCGCUGGUGCAGAUCCUGGGCCUGACCUUCGCCAUGACCAUGUACUGCCAAGUGGUCAAGGCAGACACCUACUGCGCGUAGGCCGCCCACCGCCCGCUUCUCUGCCAAAAGGACGCCCACGGGGAGAUGGCCGCACCCACAGCUGCCUUUCCCACCACCAGCCUCGGUGCUCUGCCCCAUGCUGGGAGGAGGGAGGGAGGGACAGGUGCCUGGAGCCCCCGGAACCCUGUUUCUGGAAGGCCCUAGCUCAGGUGGCUUCAGGGCCUCCGGACCCCCCCUGGGAGGGGUGGCCACGUGCUGGCUGCGGAACCCAGGGCAGGGGUGGGAGGGGCCUCCAGCACUUUUUAUAUUUACGUAUUCUCCAAAGCAGUGUUCACACGGGAGCCAGCCUGUGGCCCCCAGCCUCCUGGAAAACAGGUUGGCGCUGGAGGAGCCGGGUCUUGGCAUCCUGGAGGUGGCCCCACUGGUCCUGGUGCUCCAGGCGGGGCCGUGGACCCCUCACCUACAUUCCAUAGUGGGCCCGUGGGGCUCCUGGUGCAUCUUAAUAAAGUGUGAGCAGCAA